ACUUCCGGGUGAGUGCAAGGGGAGGGCAGCAAGGAGGGGGGGCCACCCACUACCUCGCGCCCCCGCCCUGCGGGUGUCUCGCGCGCGUUCCGUGCGUGUGAGUGUGUGGGUCUGUCUCGCUCCAGAAGUGCGUGCCCGCGCGCUGCGCCUUGCGCUUUUUCCCCUCCCUCGCCCCUUCCUGGUCCUCCCACCCUCCUCGGCUCCCUCCUUUCCCAGCAAACGCCGCCCCUCCCGCGCCCUGGCUCAGGCUCUGGCGCCGCCGCAGCCGUCGCCGCCCGGUGAGUCUCGCGCCGCUACAGCCGGCGCGCGCCAAGCUGCUUGCUCCUCCCCCCUCCCCUUUUCCUUGGGCAGGCGGGGAAGGGGGGGUCCACGAUGUGACUGUGUGUGUGUCCGUCCCGGAACCGGAAGUGGUUGUGGAGGAGCGGGCGAUGGGAAGGAAUGGGGGGGUUUAGGGGGCGGGUGCCUGUCUGGUGGGUGGCAGAGUUCAGCUCCCUGGAGGGGAAGGAGGGACGUCCCAAGGAAGGGUCUUUGAGAAAGGGGUAGGGGACGACAUCAGGAGAAGGCUCCCAGGAACUGUCUCAGGGGAGCGAAGGUUUUGAGGGGACAGCUGGGGUCUCCAGUAGAUAGACCACGGUGCAGGCUGAGGGAGGUACUUCUUGGCACAAGGCCUCGGGUAGGCAGGGGGCGAAGUCCUCGAAGAAGUGGGGGGAAGGCUAGAGGAAGUGGCUGGGCCUGAACUGGCACUGUGCCUGCCACAAGGUCUUGUGCAUCCCCCAGCCCUCAGCUUUGCCUUCUGAAGCCACUCCUCAGGGGCACAGACCCUCCUCCUCCUCCAUCUCUAAUGUUCUCUGACCCCUGGUUACCUGUGGCCUGGGAACGAACAAGGACCAGUCUCUGAGCCUAGGAGUGAAACCCAAACGCUGGUGAUAGAAUUCGUCUUAGUUUCUGGGAAUUGGAUUUAUUUCUCUUGUAUCCACGUAGAGGGUAGCACUAGACUGCUGUUAUUAUAUCCACCCGUCUUUGGAUUGCUGGCUGGGGGGUCUGCCUGCCUUCCAGACUGACUGCUGACAAAUAAUUCCUGAGGUUCUCCACAGUUCUCUGGUGGCUGCACCCUGCCUGGCCCCUGUAACCUAGACAAUUUGUUUACAGAAAGUUCAGGAGCCCUGGAAAGGAGAAGGAAUAAGACGGCAGGAGGAAGAGAGAGAGAGGGUAGAAUGGAAGAAUCUCACUUCAAUUCUAACCCGUACUUCUGGCCUUCUAUCCCCACAGUCUCAGGUCAGAUCGAGAACACAAUGUUCAUCAACAAGAUGAAGGAUCAGCUGUUGCCAGAGAAGGGCUGUGGUCUGGCCCCACCUCACUACCCCACCUUGCUGACAGUGCCUGCCUCAGUGUCCCUGCCCUCAGGCAUCAGUAUGGACACAGAGUCCAAGUCAGACCAGCUGACCCCACACAGCCAAGCGUCCGUUACCCAGAAUAUCACGGUGGUCCCUGUGCCGUCUACAGGACUGAUGACUGCUGGAGUCUCCUGUUCUCAGAGGUGGAGAAGAGAAGGGAGUCAAUCAAGGGGUCCGGGUUUGGUAAUCACGUCCCCCUCAGGCUCUCUUGUGACCACAGCAUCAUCAGCUCAGACCUUCCCCAUUUCGGCUCCCAUGAUUGUCUCAGCUCUUCCCCCUGGCUCACAAGCCCUGCAGGUUGUCCCUGACCUCUCCAAGAAGGUAGCAUCGACCCUAACCGAGGAAGGAGGCGGAGGUGGUGGUGGAGGUGGCAGUGUGGCUCCUAAGCCACCCCGGGGCCGGAAGAAGAAGCGGAUGCUGGAAUCAGGGCUGCCCGAGAUGAAUGACCCUUAUGUCCUCUCCCCUGAGGAUGAUGAUGACCAUCAGAAAGACGGCAAGACCUACAGGAGCGAAGGGAACUGCGGCACAGGAAAUGGACAGAGCCUUGGGCUCAUGGAUUCAGUUCCCGGCUCCACCACGAAUUUGCUGUGUGACCCUGGGUGCCGGAUGUGCUCACUGACAUUCUACUCCAAGUCGGAGAUGCAGAUCCACUCCAAGUCACACACCGAGACCAAGCCCCACAAGUGCCCACAUUGCUCCAAGACCUUCGCCAACAGCUCCUACCUGGCCCAGCACAUCCGUAUACACUCAGGGGCUAAGCCCUACAGUUGUAACUUCUGUGAGAAAUCCUUCCGCCAGCUCUCCCACCUUCAGCAGCACACCCGGAUCCACUCCAAGAUGCACACGGAGACCAUCAAGCCCCACAAGUGCCCGCACUGCUCCAAGACCUUCGCCAACACCUCCUACCUGGCCCAGCACCUCCGUAUCCACUCGGGGGCCAAGCCCUACAACUGUUCCUACUGCCAGAAGGCCUUCCGCCAGCUCUCCCACCUCCAGCAGCACACACGAAUCCACACUGGUGAUAGACCAUACAAAUGUGCACACCCAGGCUGUGAGAAAGCCUUCACACAACUCUCCAAUCUGCAGUCCCACAGACGGCAACACAACAAAGAUAAACCCUUCAAGUGCCACAACUGUCAUCGGGCGUACACGGAUGCAGCCUCACUAGAGGUGCACCUGUCUACGCACACAGUGAAGCAUGCCAAGGUGUACACCUGCACUAUCUGCAGUCGGGCAUACACAUCAGAAACAUACCUUAUGAAACAUAUGCGCAAACACAACCCGCCUGAUCUUCAGCAACAGGUGCAGGCAGCAGCAGCAGCGGCAGCAGUGGCCCAGGCCCAGGCUCAAGCUCAAGCCCAGGCUCAGGCUCAGGCUCAAGCCCAGGCCCAGGCCCAGGCCUCCCAGGCAUCACAGCAGCAGCAGCAGCAGCAGCAGCAGCAGCAGCAGCAGCAGCAACAGCCACCACCACACUUCCAGUCUCCUGGGGCAGCCCCCCAGGGUGGGGGUGGUGGGGACAGCAAUCCCAACCCUCCACCCCAGUGUUCCUUUGACCUGACCCCGUAUAAGACGGCGGAGCAUCAUAAGGACAUCUGCCUCACUGUCACCACCAGCACCAUCCAGGUGGAGCACCUGGCCAGCUCUUAGAGAUCCGUGCUGCCACCCACUGGGAAGAGGAAGAAGUAGUCCUGGUGUCUUCUUUCUCCAACUCUUGGUGGGAAAAGUCCUUUUCUUCCUUGACAGGCCUUGGCUCCAUCUCCUUGGGCCUCUGUCACGGCUUUCCUUCACAGGAUACCAUCCUUUUUCUGAACUCUUCUUCAAAAGGAACAUCAGCCCUCCUGAUUGCAAAGGAAUACUGAGCUGAUGGUGUCAUCCAGCAGCCUCCCCUCCCAAGCAAAGCUUCUAAAACUGGGGGUCGGUGCUCAAGGGAAGGAUUUGCUAUGACCUCAUAGAACCUUGUCCAGUGUGGCCACUUACCCUAUCCUUACCCUCCUUAUCCUCAAAGUUUGGGCUGAUGUAAGACUAGAGGCUGGCCCUCCCAGAUAACAGAGAAAAGGGAGCCCCAAAUGCAACCAGCCUCUUGUUCUAUUCUUGCCUGCAAAAGAACAGAGGUUUCUCAAAUGCCUCAGUCCCUGAGAGCCAUUUCUUCCCCUACAUCGUCUCACUUUGCUUCCUAUUGACUGCUGGUAGAAGGAGAUUUGGGGUAGGGGCUAGACCUCCUUUUAUUUGAAGGGGGCAAGGGCUGAGAUGUGGUCCCCAAGGGGCCAGAAAUUCCCAAGUUGGUCACAGGUGGCUUAGAAGUGUGUGUUAUGGUUUUACGGAUUUCCUUGAAGCCUCUCUCCUUCUCUGCCUACAAAGACCCUAUACUCUCAGUCUCCCCAACCCACCCCCAAGGAGCUGUGGGAGGCUUUGUGUUAUCUGUGAAACUCCAAAACAGGGGUGUUGCGGAGAAGGGAGAGUUCAAGGCAAACGCAAGGACUGGACUUAGCUCCCUAGGUGCCACAGUCAGAUGCCGGACACGGAUUUAUAUAUAAAUAUAUAUAUAUAAAUAUAUUAUACUCACUCAUCACGGCCAUCUUUGUUGUAACCAUUUCUGUGUUUAUAAAUGCAUUAUCUCUGAGAAUUUUCAUAUUUGAUGUUUUGUUUAUUUUUGUCCUUUUUUUCCCUCUCUCCACCCCUGUCCUCUAGCCACAGCAUUUUUCUUUUUGUCUUUUUUUUUUUUUUUUAAAUCAUGGCAGAUUUCAGAGGAAAGGAAAUUAAAAAAAAAAUCAGGAAACCAGUUGUUAUAAAGUAAUUUAAAAAUGAAGAAAAAAAGAAAAAAACUUAUGUACAAACCAAGGGGUGUUUUUAGAACAUUGUAUAGAAAUAAAUUCAUGUAAAAGGA